GUCACUGGCAGCCCUGUCCUUCCUAGAGGGACUGGAACCUAAUUCUCCUGAGGCUGAGGGAGGGUGGAGGGUCUCAAGGCAACGCUGGCCCCACGACGGAGUGCCAGGAGCACUAACAGUACCCUUAGCUUGCUUUCCUCCUCCCUCCUUUUUAUUUUCAAGUUCCUUUUUAUUUCUCCUUGCGUAACAACCUUCUUCCCUUCUGCACCACUGCCCGUACCCUUACCCGCCCCGCCACCUCCUUGCUACCCCACUCUUGAAACCACAGCUGUUGGCAGGGUCCCCAGCUCAUGCCAGCCUCAUCUCCUUUCUUGCUAGCCCCCAAAGGGCCUCCAGGCAACAUGGGGGGCCCAGUCAGAGAGCCGGCACUCUCAGUUGCCCUCUGGUUGAGUUGGGGGGCAGCUCUGGGGGCCGUGGCUUGUGCCAUGGCUCUGCUGACCCAACAAACAGAGCUGCAGAGCCUCAGGAGAGAGGUGAGCCGGCUGCAGGGGACAGGAGGCCCCUCCCAGAAUGGGGAAGGGUAUCCCUGGCAGAGUCUCCCGGAGCAGAGUUCCGAUGCCCUGGAAGCCUGGGAGAAUGGGGAGAGAUCCCGGAAAAGGAGAGCAGUGCUCACCCAAAAACAGAAGAAGCAGCACUCUGUCCUGCACCUGGUUCCCAUUAACGCCACCUCCAAGGAUGACUCCGAUGUGACAGAGGUGAUGUGGCAACCAGCUCUUAGGCGUGGGAGAGGCCUACAGGCCCAAGGAUAUGGUGUCCGAAUCCAGGAUGCUGGAGUUUAUCUGCUGUAUAGCCAGGUCCUGUUUCAAGACGUGACUUUCACCAUGGGUCAGGUGGUGUCUCGAGAAGGCCAAGGAAGGCAGGAGACUCUAUUCCGAUGUAUAAGAAGUAUGCCCUCCCACCCGGACCGGGCCUACAACAGCUGCUAUAGCGCAGGUGUCUUCCAUUUACACCAAGGGGAUAUUCUGAGUGUCAUAAUUCCCCGGGCAAGGGCGAAACUUAACCUCUCUCCACAUGGAACCUUCCUGGGGUUUGUGAAACUGUGAUUGUGUUAUAAAAAGUGGCUCCCAGCUUGGAAGACCAGGGUGGGUACAUACUGGAGACAGCCAAGAGCUGAGUAUAUAAAGGAGAGGGAAUGUGCAGGAACAGAGGCGUCUUCCUGGGUUUGGCUCCCCGUUCCUCACUUUUCCCUUUUCAUUCCCACCCCCUAGACUUUGAUUUUACGGAUAUCUUGCUUCUGUUCCCCAUGGAGCUCCGAAUUCUUGCGUGUGUGUAGAUGAGGGGCGGGGGACGGGCGCCAGGCAUUGUCCAGACCUGGUCGGGGCCCACUGGAAGCAUCCAGAACAGCACCACCAUCUAGCGGCCGCUCGAGGGAAGCACCCGCCGGUUGGCCGAAGUCCACGAAGCCGCCCUCUGCUAGGGAAAACCCCUGGUUCUCCAUGCCACACCUCUCUCCAGGUGCCCUCUGCCUCUUCACCCCACAAGAAGCCUUAUCCUACGUCCUUCUCUCCAUCUAUCGGACCCCAGUUUCCAUCACUAUCUCCAGAGAUGUAGCUAUUAUGCGCCCGUCUACAGGGGGUGCCCGACGAUGACGGUGCCUUCGCAGUCAAAUUACUCUUCGGGUCCCAAGGUUUGGCUUUCACGCGCUCCAUUGCCCCGGCGUGGCAGGCCAUUCCAAGCCCUUCCGGGCUGGAACUGGUGUCGGAGGAGCCUCGGGUGUAUCGUACGCCCUGGUGUUGGUGUUGCCUCACUCCUCUGAGCUCUUCUUUCUGAUCAAGCCCUGCUUAAAGUUAAAUAAAAUAGAAUGAAUGAUA